CUGGGCAAUAGAGGGAGACUCCAUCUCAAAAAAAAAACAAAAACCAAGUUACAGUUCAAUGUUAUAGAUGUUAUAAAAUAAGUAGCAGAGACAGGGUAUUCAAACCUUUUUUUAGGGAAGAGUUCUUGGAGGAAGAGUAACCUGAGCUUAUUUUUGAAAGAAGACUAGGUCUUAUGUGUGGACAAUUCUGGACAUGGAGUCAGAAGAACUGAAUUUGAACCCCAGCUUAGCCACUUACUAGCUGUCUGACUUGGACAGGUUGUUUAAGUACUCUGUGAAUCUCAGUUUUUUCCCAUGUAAAGUGGGGACAGUCAUAUCUAUAUCCACCUUUGAAAUUCAAUACAUUUGAAAGAAGCUCAUAAAUGUGAUAUACAAGUAUUCUGUUUUUUAGCUCAUAAAUGUGGUAUACAAGUAUUAUAUUCUGUUUUUUUCCAAGCCAAACUGUAUCCAGCUUUAUUAAAGAUACUGUCCGUAAACAAUCAUGGCAUUUCAGACAGGACAUGUGCAGACAAUCGUUAACAGUAUACAACAACUUUCAAACUCCCUUCUUUAAUGGCCUACCAAAAAUCAGAAAGCCACUAUAAAACCCAAUGAAGUCUUCAUCUGAUGCUCUGAACAGGGAAAGUUUAGAGUGAGGGUUGACAUUUCACAUUUAGCAUGUUGUUUAACAACUUUUCAUAAGCUGACCCUGACUUUCAGGAAGUGAAGUGAAAGUGACAGAAUUUACCUGAAGAUCCACAAUCUAGAAACGGAACCACUGCUCUUUUGACAGGUGCCAUCUCAGUGGCAUCACUGGAAAGUCCAGAUUGCCUGACACACUGGUAACCAAUGAUUAGGGGUCAGGUCCCAACAGAUGUCUGGGUUUAAGGGAGUUAAGUCUAGCUGAAAGGUAGAAAGGGAGAAGAGGACAUAAAAACAAAUUUGUUUUUCCAUACCACAAAGCUUUUGUGCCAAGGUGGCCAUGUGUGUCAAAGUCAGGGAAUCCCUGCUCCUGGGAGCCAAGAGGAAGUCUCUCAAAACUGGAAGGGAAAGGUGUUUUCCCCACAUCAAUCCAGCUUUGGAGACAUUUUAUUAGUGACAUAAGCCCCUUCCUCUCAAAACAACAAGGACAUGUUCUGUGUGCUAACAACAUAGCUUAAAAAAGUAAAACAAAAUUCUGCAUUUUUAUAAAACUUGAUUAAAAAUAGUAUUUCAAACUGUACAGUCACCAGAAGUACAUGGUUAUUAAAAAUGCACACACUUCGCUUGGCAUCUCCAGCACCUUCAGCUUUCUGUCCCUGGUCUGUUUUGGCAUCUCCAUUUUCUGUAGGGUUAUCCCCAUCCUGGCCAGCCUCAGCUUUUCCCUUUUUCCCUUUGGGUACCUUCUCUCCCUUCUUUGCAGGGGCUUUUUUGGCCUGGGCUCUAUCUUUGGAGGAGCAGGUUUAGCAGACAACCUUGUGGAUCUUCUCUGUGGUUCAUCCUUCACCUUGGCUUUAUCUCCUUUAGCAUCCCCUUCAGCCUUUCUUGGGCAUGGUGGCGGCGACAGUGACGGCAGCGGGACGUAGGCACUGGGCGUGGGAUGCAGCGGAGCACAGGCUUUGGUUGGUCUGGGGGUCGUUCUCACCUCUUCUUCUGGUUUUUGUUUUUUACUUAUUCAUUGACAAUUAUAUUUUGACAGAUUGUAGCAUCAGUUUUCUUACCCAAACCAGAAAUAAGUGAGGAAAAUAUUGAGUAUAUUAGUGUGUAGACAUCAUUUAUGAAGUGCUAACACUAUAAACAUGUAUCAAGGCAAAUAUUUUAAAGUUCAGAUCCAUGAAACUUUGAUUCUGUGCUAUUGUACAAGAUACUGCUUAAGGUACCUAAAUGAAUGGUAUCUGAAAAAUUAUUGAGUUUGCUUCUGAGUGGCUUGGAUAGCAACCAGCUGAACUAGAAAGAGCCUCAUUUCUUGUCAGAAGACUUAUGCUUGCAUCCAAGUGAUGCAACUUAUGUCUGUGCUGCUGAAGGUUAUUUAACAUUUCAGAGUUUCAUUUUCUCCAUCAGUAAAGGAGAAAAAUAAUAGUUACUUUGUAGACUGUGAAUUAGGAAUAAACUGGAUAAAUUGCUUACCACUAGCUUUUAUCAGUUAAAAGUUAAUUUAUGGAAUAUUAAACAAAUUUCCAUUUAAUUACAUUUCUUUAGAGAAACUUGCUCUAAAUGGUGGGUGGGGGGAAUUCUGUUAUUUAUGCUUUACUGACACUGAUGAUAUUUUACCUCCUUCUUCCAGUUAUUCCUCAAUAAUUUUGUAAGGUGAGUUUAAAUCUCAGCUAUUGUACUUCCUUGCAGUGUGACCUUCAAAGUUACUUAAUCUUUCUAUAACUUAUUUUCUCCAUCUAUUAGGUGGAGAAUUAAUGGCAUUUAUAUUAUAUAGUUACUUAAUCUUUCUAUAACUUAUUUUCUCUAUCCAUUAGAUGGAGACAUAAUGGUAUUUACAUUAUAUAAUUGUUAGGAAGUAACUAAAGUGCUUAGUUCAGUGUUUGGCACAUAGUAUGAUUUCAGAAAAUGGUAGUGCUAUGGACUGAGUGUAUCCCACCAAAAUUCAUAUGUUGAAACCCUAAUCCUCAGUGUGAUGUUUGGGGUGGGAUUUUUGGGAAGUAAUUAGGUCAUUAGGAUGGAGCUCUAUAAGUGCCUGUAUAAGAAGAGACACCAGAGAGCUUACUUCCUCUCUCUCUGCUUUCCACUAUGUGAGGAUACAGUGAGAAGAGGGCCAUCUGCAAACCAGGAAGCUGACUGUCACCAGACACCAGAUCUGCUAGUACCUUGAUCUUGGACUUCCCAGCCUCCAGACCUGUGAAAAAUAAAUGUUUGUGGUAUUCUGUUAUGUACACAGCAGCCUGAGCUGACUAAGAUGGAUAGCAUUGCUAUUGUCACUUUCAUUUUAUAAAUGAGAAGGUGAAUACAGAUUUAGAAACCUGAUUAGAUUCAUAGUAAGAGGCAAGGAUGGGAUUCAAUCCAGGUUUGUGUGAUGCCAAAGACUUUACUGUUUAUUCUUUUACCAGGCUACAUUUUGUAAUUAACAUUUCAUUUGUAUGGAAACGUAUUCUGAAAUGCUGUAGAGUGCUUGGAAGUAAUUUGUUAUUCUUGGGUAUUUAAAACUUUCAGUGAUGUUUUACUAACCGUUUACAUAAACUUGAAACUAAAUUGGUUAGGGAAAGAAAUCUUUGGCCUGGCCUCCCUGUGAUCAGACAGUUUUAGGGCAGAUAUUCUGGGGUGGUAGUCAGUGGUUAGUAAAAAGAAAAUUGUGUGUGUGUGUUUGUGUGUGAGUGUAUUUUCUCCUAAACAGCUUCAUUGAAGUAAAAUUGGCAUACAGUAAGUGAUACAAAUUUUAUGUACAAUUUGCUAAGUUUUGACAUACAUAUACACCCAUGAAACCAUCACCACAAAGCAGAUGGUGAACAUAUCCAUCACCUCCCAAGUUUCUUGGUGCCCCUUUGAAGUCUUUCCCUCCUCAUUCUCCUCAUAUCCCCCCCAUUUAAGCAACCACCUAUCGGCUUUUCUAUCACUAUAGAUUAAACAAUGGUCAGAUCAAUCAGGAUUCAGUCAGUUCACCUCUCAGCUGUAGUUUGAUCGUCUGUGAAACAGGGAUUCUACCAUCUUCCCAAAGGACCAUUGGAGAAGAUUAGGAUUAAUGUGUAUAAAGAGCCUAGCAUAAUGUCUCUUGCAUAGUAGGCCCUCAGUCCCUGGAAGCCAGUAUUACCAGCAAGCUUUCACUUGGUGGUCUAGAGUACAUUUAGGAGUUCAGAGUGCCAAAAUGCAUUUCUGUCACUUAGAGCUCCUGUUCUCUUCCACUGAAUGGGCUUCCAGUGUUUUUGAAACAGGAAAAUUUACAUUUAGGCAGCUUAAGGCCCUAAGGGACGUUCUGUUGCUCCUACCUUCCCUCCCUCAUGCCCAGUGUUACACAUGCUAUUAAUUAUGAACAGAUGUUCUUCAAAAAUAAGCAAAGAUCUCCACAGCAGGUUUUUGCAUUCUUUAUGCCUAUGUUUAAGUCUGGCAUUGUGAUCAAGCUGCAUAAGCAAUGAGUUUGUAGUCAGAGUUCUGGGUUUUAGUUCCUAUUCUGCCUUGGGCAAAUCAUAAAAUCUUUCUGAGCCUCAGUUUUCUCAGUGUGAAGUGGUGGUGGUGGAGUCAUACCUCAGAAGUUUGUUGAGAGGAUCAAAGGAGAAUUCUGAAAGUGAAUUGUAUGAUGAGGUUAUAGUUCAUCUGCAUCCUCCCAUGACUGCCUCACAGUGUCAGAACUUUGUAAAAGGAUCAGGCAGCAUUUAAAUCUGAUAUCUUACAGGUUUUUAAUAUAAGUAUUUUAAAUUGGGCUCUGCUAAUAGAAUAAAGUGGCAAAAAUAAAUAACAACAGAUAAAUAAUUUGUGAAAUUAUUUGCUCAAGGUUAAAAGUGCUUCCAUUUUAAAGUCAGAGAAACUUUAAUUCAGAUAUUAGUUAAGUAGCUGUGUGACCAUGGACAAGUUAUUUAAUUUCUCUGAGCCUUAAAUUCUCACCUGUUAAUAAGGCAUAUCUGUUCUACCUCAGAGGGUUGUUGGGAGGAUUAGAAAUAAUAUGUGUACCAUAGUUGGCAUAUAGCAGAUGCCCAGUGACGCUAGCUUCAUUCCUUCCAUUUCCAAAAUUGGUAGAUUUGUGGAUUCGUUGAACUAUUCCUGAAGGGAUGACUUUUGCCUUCUCUAUUCCGUGAUGCGGUUCAGCACAGGUUAGCUGUUAGGUAGUGUCUCAGGUUUCCCAUUCAAGUCUGUAAAUGUCAUUUGAGCUUUAUGGUGCUAGCAGUUAUUGCAAAGGAAUUUUUUUUUUUUUUUUAAAUAAUGGGAGGCACCUAUGCUUUGCUUUUGUACUUUCUCAUCAAUUCUCAUUGCUCUGUCUAGCUAGAGAUACUUUGUAUUGUGAGAGCCAGGGAAACCAGGGGCCAUUUUCUUGUCUCUCUGUGUUUAUUUGGGUUGGAGGAUUGUCUAAAAGUUCCCUAGUGAAUAAAGUAGAUUUGCUGAGUUCAGAUUCUUCCCUCCUGGGUGAGCCCAGGAUCGAACUACUGGGCAAGAAAAGAAAUAGGAAGAUGUGGAGAAAACUGGUGAGUUCUGCUUGUAAAGUUGUCAGGAUCUUUGAGUUGGGGGGCAUGUAGAAAACAGUUGAUUCCCCAUUUCCGUCUUCAUUUCCAGAGCCUGUACACUCCAACACAAAGGGAGCUUUAAGAUGGAGGUCUGCAUUGUAAUUUCCUAGAAAUUACUGCUUCUGGUAACCGCUCAUUCAGUUUUCACCUCUUUGCUGCAGUAGAUGAAACAAUGGGGACAAUAAAACCAUUUAUCUGAUGGCUGUAGCCUCAAUGGGAUGUUUGUUUUAAUAAUGGUAUAAUUUGCAGGGUUCAUAAAUUGUGAUUUUAUUCUCAUGGAAAUAACUGCCCGGUGGUAUUUGGAUUCUCAGGUCUCCUGUUGUGAAUAAUUUCGCUAACAUUCUGGCUGACAAUUCCCUUUAUUCUACACUUCGAUUUAGAUUGUUCAUGCUGGUUGGGUAAUUAGCCCAGAACAGAGCCAGUUUUUUUCAGUUUGGGGAUGGCAGGUGGUUACUAGGUAACUAGAAGAUCUUCUGAAUGGAGAAGAAACUCUGCUUAGGGAUUCAAGGCAAAUACCCAGGUUUGUUUUGAUUAUCUGGGAUUUAAAAAAUUAUCUAAUACCAAAAUAUUUGAUGAAAAUUGAAAUUUAAUUCAUCUGAAUAUUUGUUUUCCAUGACACCAAACAACCCAUUAUAUUUGGAAUAUCCUAUGUUUGAGUUUUAAAUUUUCAUGUGCAUGUUUUGGCAGGGAAUAUCCACAGAGGGCAGAGGCUGAUAAUAGCUACACAUGCUAGACAUUGCCAUAGGUGUUUUACUUACAUUAUGUCUAAUUUUUUUUUUUUUGACAUAGUUUGACUCUUGUUGCUCAGGCUGGAGUGCAGUGGCACGAUCUCGGUUCACUGCAACCUCCACCUCCCAGGUUCAAGUGAUUGUCCUGCCUCAGCCUCCCGAGUAGCUGGGAGUAUAGGUUCCUGCCACUACACCCAGCUAAUUUUUAUGUUUUAGUAGAGACAGGGUUUCACCACGUUGACCAGGCUGGUCUCAAACUCCUGACCUCAGGUGAUCCACUUGCCUCAGCCUCCCAAAGUGCUGGGAUUACAGGUGUGAGCCACCACACCCGGCCAUUUCUAAAUCUUAAUGAGAACUCUGAUAGGUAGGUAUUGUUUCCAUGUUACCCAUGUAAAAAGUUAAGACACGUUUAGUAACUAAAUUAAGGGAUUCAGCUAAUUAGUGGCAGACAGUUUACCAGAUUCAAAGCUUAUCCUAGGCUUUCAAUUACAGGGUAAGACAUUCUGAAGAUACAUUCAAGUUGAAAUUAAACUGUUAGAUAUUACAGCAGUUGGCUCAAAAAUAAUAUUAUAUGUGAAUUAAUACCUAUCAUCAGAUGUAUAUAUCUGAUUGUUCUUCCUGUCAUUUAAUCUUGUUUUACAGCAGUAACAUACAUGGAAUAUUUUGAUUAUCUCACCAAAAUUAAAGGACUUCUAGGCAUAAUCCUGUUUUAAGAAUUCUUUAAAAGGCUCCAAAGCAUGGCGUAGUCACUGGAAAUAGCCUCAGACUUGGGUUUCAAAAUCUUGGCACUGCCAUUUAUUGGGUUAUCUUGGAUAAACCUUUUGACCAUCAUUGGAUAACCCUUACUCUUGUAUGAGCCUUAUUUUGCUCAUCUGCAAAAUAGGGAUAUGAUACACACUUUACAGGGAUGUUAGGGUUAAUGUAUGUGGUGGGGUCUAGUAUAUGACUGUAAUAUGUUGGUUUCCUUUAUUGAGUAAUGCUACUGCUAGUAGAGUAUCAGGGGAUAAUUUGGUGCUUUCAUCAUUGGCCUCAGGAUUUAUUAAAAGAUGGCCAACAUCGGAUGGGCACGGUGGCUCACACCUGUAAUCCCAGCACUUUGGGAGGCUGAGAUGAGCGGGUCACUGGAGGUCAGGAGUUUGAGACUAGCCUGGCCAAAAUGGUGAAACCUUUUCUCUACUAAAAAAAAAAAAAAAAAAAAAAAAAUGCCAGGUGUAGUGGCACAUCCCAGCUACUUGGGAGGCUGAGGCAGGAGAAUCACUUGAACCUGGAAGGCAGAGGUUGCAGUGAGCCAAGAUCAUGUCAUCGCACUCCAGCUUGGGCGACAAGAGGGAAACUCCAUCUCAGAAAAAAAGAUGGCCAACUUCAAGUGCCAUUAUGUUAUAUUUUCAUGUGAUGCUGUUAAACUAAUAGAGCUGAUUUUUCUCCAGGAACUUGCUGUUCCAUCUAGGUAAUUUGUUUAAGGGGCAGUUAGAUAGAUGAUGUAUUUUUUUAUACUCUCUUGGUCAAGAGAGUGAGUGCAUAUGUGGAAAGGGCAUUGGAUUUGUGAUUAUACAAACUUGGUGGGAGGUCCAGCAUUGCUGUUUACUAGCUAAGUUUCAUGGGACAACUGACUUUCUCUGUUUGAAACUUGGGAUAGAGAUAAUAAUAGCCAACUUUCCCAUCUGUUGUGAAGAUCAAAUGAGAUAAUGAAUGUGAAAAUGCCUUUUAAAUUGGAAAAAUGCCAGCCAAGAUAGUAACUAUUAUGUGACAUUCAUAAUUAGUAUUAAGUGGGGCUUAGAGAAUUAAUUACUUUUUUUUUUGAGACAGGGUCUUGCUCUGUCACCCAGGCUGGAGUACAGUGGUGGGCUCAUGGCUCACUGUUGCCUCCACCUCCUGGGCUUAGUGAUCCCCCUGCCUCGCCUCCUGAGUAGCUGGGACCACAGGUGUGCAACGCCAUGCCCUGCCCCCACCCCUGCCCCUUGGUAUUUUGAGACGAAUCUUGCUCUGUCACCCAGGCUGGAGUGCAGAGUCCCGCUCAUAGCUUACUGCAGCGUGGAACUCCUGGACAUAGUGAUCCUCUCACCUCAGUAUCCUGAGUAGCUGGGAUUAUAGGCAUGUACCACCAUGCCUGGCUCAUUCUUGAAUUUUUUGUAGAGACAGGGUCUCUAUGUUGCCCAGACUGGUUUCGAACUCCUGUCCUCCAGCCAACCUCCUGUCUUCCAGCCAACCUCCUGUCUUGGCCUCCCAAAGUGCUGGGAUUACGGGCAUGAGCCACUGUGCCCCGUCGGAAUUCACUGCUAUUUUAAGAGGCAAAUUUAAAAUUUCCCUUGAACUAUAUAAAGACAUUUUGAUGAGUUUUAUUAUGGUAGUCCUUGGGGACAGCAGAAGAAAAGAGGCCAGAAUGAUGUUCUGGGUAGAUAAAGUAUUGAGUGAAUGUAACUGCAUAGUGGAAAUGAGAAAAUGGGGUGUGGUACUACUGUGAGGCAGGCCCAGAGGACUUAGAGAAGAGCUUAGACUUGAGAUUUGGAUCUUGGUCUAAUCUUGAUCCCUAGAACAAGGAAGUGGGAGGCUCCUUGAUUAGAAAAACUUAGGACACAGGGUAGUGUGUGGAGAACUGUUGAGGAAUAGGGAUAGAGGUAACAACUGUAGCUUCCGUCAUGAUGACACUCAAGUUGAAAUCCUGGUUUUAAGCCUUCUAGGAGUAUGUACAGAAGUUAAAAUAGAUUUUUUUUCAUUCCUCUUUCUACCUUCUAACAGUUAAGUGUGUCCAUUUUUAGGGGAAAGUUCCAAGUGCGUCUUGCGAUUAUUGUGCAUGAAUCCAGUGGUGUCUCUCAGGAUCCUCAGUCUUCCACAAUGAACCCUGUUUACAGCCCCGUGCAGCCUGGGGCUCCUUAUGGCAACCCUAAGAACAUGGCCUACACGGGUUACCCCACAGCCUAUCCAGCAGCUGCCCCUGCCUACAAUCCCAGCCUGUACCCCACCAAUAGUCCCAGUUAUGCUCCAGAGUUUCAGUUCCUGCAUUCAGCUUAUGGACACCAUGAAGCAACUCUGCUGAUGAAACAGGCCUGGCCACAGAACUCGUCUUCCUGUGGCACUGAAGGCACCUUCCACCUCCCAGUGGACACCGGGACCGAGAACCGAACUUACCAAGCAUCCUCUGCGGCUUUCAGAUAUACUGCGGGGACACCAUACAAGGUCCCACCGACCCAGAGUAACACUGCUCCACCCCCCUACUCCCCAUCACCCAACCCCUAUCAGACGGCCAUGUAUCCAAUCAGAAGUGCCUACCCCCAGCAGAAUCUGUAUGCCCAGGGAGCCUACUACACACAGCCGGUGUAUGCUGCCCAGCCUCAUGUCAUCCACCAUACCACGGUCGUCCAGCCCAACAGCAUUCCCUCUGCUAUCUACCCAGCACCUGUUGCCGCCCCGAGGACCAACGGUGUGGCCAUGGGCAUGGUGGCAGGCACCACCAUGGCAAUGUCAGCAGGUACCCUGCUGACUACACCCCAGCACACGGCGAUUGGGGCACACCCUGUCUCCAUGCCAACAUAUAGGGCCCAAGGAACCCCUGCGUACAGCUACGUGCCCCCACACUGGUAAAGCCUGCAGCCCAUCCAAAUCUGGAGUCACACAUUGUAUGCAACUACUCAAGUCUUACACCGGUGCUGGAGCAGUUCCCUAGCAGCACCACCUCUAUUUGCAAGAAGAGACAACGGAAGUGCAAGGGUCACUUUAUGCAUCUUUAAUGGUUUUGAUUUUUAUUUUUGGUUUUUGUAAAAGCUGCUUUUUCUAAUCUCCUGCCUCUCCCCAACUGUCCCCCUCUUAGCCCCUGCCCUUCCAGCUCUAUCCCCUUCCUCCUACCUGACCAGGCCAUGUCCUCUCUGCUCUUCCCUAAGUGUCCUGUCCCUGGGGAUCCCAGUCUAGAGGCAAGCAGAGAGUAGGGUUUAUUGCAGUGGUUCAUCUGAAGGCUGGAUUCCAUUUGAAGAGCAUAAACAGAUGUGGUCCAGGGUAGGAACUCAGAGCUGUUGAGCAGGCUACAUCUCUAGGGGAGUGUUCUGGUUGUUUUUUCUUAAGCAAGAUUAGUUCAGGACAUUCCCAUGUCCCAGACACAAAUGAAAUGUCUCCUGAGAACCAUUGCAACAGACCAAGAACAAAACCACCUGAGUAUGUAGGCGUGUUAUUAGCAGCUUAAUACCCCAGGCUGAGAACCUGGGGAAAAAAGUCUUUAGAAUUUGGGGGAGGGUGGGGGGAGGGAGGGCAUUGUGGGGAAGGAGAGGGAAGAAGGGAGGAGCGGUGCUUGCCUCAUGGCUUUGGUUUGAAAGGUCUCUGGCCAAAGCAUCUGGCCCUGGACCUUCUGAUUUGCACAGUGAUGUUAACUGACCUGGCACUUCCUCAAAAGGUGAUUUUGUCCUUAGACCUGCCAAGCGGCUGCAGGGUGGUAGGAUCCCAGCAUCCCGAGGCCUUGGAAGGCCGGAUGCCCUGUGUCAUCCAGACUUCAGCCUCUGAGCUGUCAUGGACCCACUCUGAUGAGGAGCUUCCUCCUGAUUGGAGUGGGAACCUAGGGCAUUUCUCUCCCUUUUCUUUUGCCCUUCCCAGUGCCAGGACUCACCUGUCUGACCAUAGAGCUUGCAGGCAGGCCAAGCUCUUGGUUACCUGUGCCAUUCAUGGCCCAAGUGAAGGAACCACAUUCCAGGUGGGUGCUGGCAGCUCUGAAGGUGAGGAUAGUGAAGGAAAAGCAAUAGCAAUAAACAUUUCAUAGACUCAUGGAACUGAAGGGACCUUAGCAAUCAUCUCAUCCAUUUCCCUAUUUGGCAGAUGAGGAAACUGAGGCCCAGAGAAGCGGAAAGGACUUCCCUAGACCUUACAGUAAAUUAGCAUUAAAUGCAGCCUUCCUACCUAGUGGGCACCUUGCUUACAAAAAUUUACCUAGGGACGGAUUGGCUUGGUUUUGUAAAAAUUAAGUCGGCAGCGCCCAUACCUGGUGAGUCUGGAAUGGUCUCUGGGCUCCUGUUUCUGCUCUUUUCCUCCACGGACUCCAAAGGCGGGGGUUGAAGACUGGGCAGAGGCUACAUGGGGGCGGAUGGCAGGAACAGAAAUUGCAAAUGAAGAAAUAGCAUUUGGAAAUUCUGUGAAGACAUCUGGAACUUCCGUCCUGUACCUGACUCCACCUCCAGGAGAAGGAGCAGGUGGACUGGCCGAAAAGGAGAGGCCAUGCUUUUAGGACAGUAGCCCCUCAUCCCGAGAGGAGAGGAAGAGGAGGAAGACAGUGGGAGUCAUCAGGAGAGGAGAAUGAGGAUGAGGCCCAGGAGACAGGCUCAUCUGGGAGAAGAGGGACCCCUGGGACGAGGAGGUCCCUGCUAGUCUCAGCCAGGAGCCUGGAUUGCCCAGCAGCAGCCUCCGGCACCCAGCGCUUGGCUGGGCCAGCAGCCCCUCUGGGGGUGGGGCACGAACAUUUUAUUGUAAAAAAUGGGAUCAUUGACAACAUUUGGGACUUUAAAAAACUGCUUUCAUUUAAAAUUCAUGCAAACUUGGACAUAUCCUUACCCCAACCUCCCAUGUCUCCCUAAGGGAGGGAAAAAUCAGGAAACCCUUGGGUUGGAAGGAGCUCAGAAGCUGUCUAGCCAUUCCCAGGAGGGUAAAGCCCAUCAGCCUCCUUGGCCUAGAGCCAGGAGUUUGGGGGCCCACCUUCCUGGGCUUCCAAGGAACUUUAGGACCAGUAAGAAAAAAUUCAGCUGUUCUAAAUUAUCUGUUCUGGGUGCUGAUGAGGUUUCACUUUAAAACAAUAGAAAGUUUUCCAGUGUUAAUUCACUUUUUGCAAAUACCUCCUUCCACCCUCUUUGGUUUUGUAAAGGUGGGUGAAGGUUGUUCUAGAUUAUGUCAUACGUGUUUGAAAAAUGCCAAAAUAAUAAUAAUGAUAAUAAUAAUAGAAACCUUUGGAUUUGUCAGGUGCAUCACAGAGGUCAAAGCACUUCACGGCCUUUCAUGUACUCGCCCUGAGAGGGACAGGGUUAGAGUUAUUACAGUCAAUUGACAAAUGAGGAAACAGGUUAUGGAAGGGAACAGGCCCACAGUGAGCAGCAUGCUGGUAUCCGCUAGGCUUCCCAGAACCCUGCUGCCUCCAUGUGGGCUGGGGUGGAACCACAGAGAGGAGAAAGGAAGAAGAGGAGACCUAGGAAUGACCUUGUAACUUUUGUUCUUUCAACACCAGUAAGUAAAACUAACAGCUGGACCUCACAGUUCACAGAACAGUUGAACAUAAAUUAUCUGGUUUAACCCGAUGAAAUAGAGGUUAUUUCUCCUAUUUGAUCCAUAAGGAAAUCAAGGCUUGGAAAAGUCAAGUGACUUGCUAAUAAGUGACAGAGCCACUCGAAUCCCAGGCUGUCUGCUGUCUCGUUCCCCUCCAUCUGAUCCCCACACAGGCUCACGUACUGAAGCAUCUGUGCUCUGUGCCCUAUCUUAGCACCUACUAUGUAAUUCAAGAGCAAAGGGGGGCCCCAAGGUGAAAAUAAGGCACUGAAAGGCUGUGGUCUGGAAGAGCCCAGGUCCAGCACCCCUUUUUCAGUAUGAGCCCCAGUUCAGCCGGCCUCAGCCUCUUGCUGUGAUGGAGAUCCACAAGCCUAGCCAAGCUUGGGGAGUCACUGCAAAAGGACUGAGCCCAGGAGAGCGGGGACAGUCAUGUGCCUCUGGUAGGAUGGGCACAGUUACUGGUAAGGUCACAGAGAUCUAGUGGGAGGUACCAUAGGUAGAUACCUCCAAAGAUUCUAGAUGGCACGGUGGUCAAGCUAGACAAAAAGUCAGAGCUGGAAGGGCCGUCUCAUUGAAGGCAGGCAAGCAAGAGAGGACAAGGGAUGUAGCCGCCUGACAGUGAGCUACAGCACUGGCCCCAGGAUGCAAACCCCUCUCUCCUCCUCAUGCCACUGCCUCUCCCCAAGUGCAACACCUAUGGCCAGGAUCAGGGGUACAGAUGGCUCGUUACCAGCCAACCCUUUUGAAUUCUUCUACUUCUACCUGACCCCCUCUCCUCACUGGCCUGGGGUCAAGAAGUUUGAGUCUGGGAGCUGGAUUGCCUGCAAAUAGUGAAAGCCUGAAACAUAAUGGUUUGCCAUGUUUUGAAAAAAAAUGCAUAUUUAAUUUCUUCCUCAUGAGAUAGGACAGUUGCUGUUCUUUCUUACCUGGCAAUGACCCUAAAAUGUAUAUCCUCUUUCCUGAAUAUUUAGCAGAGACACACACACCUGUCCAGAGCGUUUUUGGUAUGCAAAGUACUUUGACAUUGGUUGCCAAAGUCCUCCAUUUUAUAGAUGAAAAAACUAAGGCUCAGGAGGCUUGAGACUUGCUAAAAGGUCACACAGCUUGGAAGUGAUUCUUCAAAUCCUCUGCUCUUUCUGCUGCCACCUGCUGGGUCUCUUGGCAAGCAUGGAGGGAGGGGCUAACUGUACUUUAUAGAGCUGGGAAGCCCAGUCUCUGAGCUGAGCAGAUUUGUAUGAACUGCUUUGGGCCAGGACCUGUAAUGAGCCCUGGGGAGGGACCCAGAGGCACAUCUAACUGGCAGCACAAGGAGGAUGAGAAUUUGCAACUAAAGGCCUCACUUGGACAAAACACUUUGGGGUCACAAUGCCCAGGACCGAAGACAUGUUCAAGGACAGCACGAGGCAUCUUUCUAUUGGGAGACCCAUGUCCUUGGUAAGCCUGCACACCUGGCUUCCUAAUCCCUGAGAGCCUGCCCACUGUCCAGAUCCAGUGAGUUGGUACAAAACGUACAGACUGAAGUCCCUGGGCUUGCUUUUCCCAUGGGUGAGGACCAGAACCAGACUCUGAGCAUCCUUACCCCUGGCCACCCGAAUUGUUCCAAGUUUGAGGUACCCCGUUCCCAGAGAUCUGGGGGUCCUUCUUUGGAGGGCUUGCUUUGUUCUGAUGGCCUUCAGAAAGGAAUCACAUGAAGUAUAAAAGGACAGGCCCCUUGGUCACCAAGUUUUGGCUCCUCAUACAGAUAGGACUCAUCCAGGUUCCCAGCGAGGCACUGACUAAGCGAGGCUCAGAGCUUCCAUAUCAAAUUCCUCAGCUUUGUUCUGUGCCCAGAGGGGGUGGGCCCCAUUCUGGGCCCUGUGAACUUUGUCUUAUAUAUCACCAUCUGUAUCAGAAUUCCUCCUCAAUUGCAGUUAAGUGAAAAUACGUGGAAGUCUGCUUUUCCAUCCUGUAUUCUCCCACAUCACUACUGGCUGUGCGGCCCCCGCUGCUUGCCAAGCUUGGGAAUCCAGAGAGGGGCAGUAGUAGAGUGGGCCAGUUGGGACCCACCCGCAGAGCUGAAGAAACACGCCAGACUAACUGAUGGGAUUCCACACCGGAGCCUCUGAGCGCACAGGCAGGCAUGCCAAGGGGGCUGCAGGGUUUGUCCUUUACUUAUCUGCCCCUUUCCUAGAAAACUCCUCGUUUCUGAAAUUAGGCAUUAUAUGGUUCCAGGACCCAGCCUUCAAAAUUCCUGGCAGGCCAGCUUCAACAUUCCAUGGCCAGCCCUGCCUAAGCCAGACUUGGGUCCCAGUCCCUCAGUCUCUCCAGUGGAUAUCUUCUGUGGUGCAUGCUGUUGAGUCCAACCCAAAGGCCAACCGAGGCACACAGGAGUUGGGACUGGCUGCCACAAAGCUAGAAAGGGACAAAACAGCACUUGCUUCCCUAUGGCCACAUGGAUAGUCCCUGGAUAUCCUUGCUGUGGUAGAGGUCCUCUACCCAUUCCAGCCACUGAUAGCAGGGGGAUUUUCCUUCCUAAGGAGAACAGAUGUAACAGCUUUGCAAAGUACCGGCCCAUAGGAAUCAAAUGGGUGAGAUCAGCUUUGGGCCUGACCCCAGCAAGACCAGCAUCUCCAGACCCCAGCCUUUCUCCUCAGGCCUAAGAGAGUCAGGGAAAGAGAGGAGACUGUCCCAGAGACCUUCUCCUCGGGUCAGCCAGAUAGUCUGGAUCUAUGGUGUGACUCAAGCUCCUCCUUACCCAGGGGGGGUAAGGCCAGGCCUCUAGCUACUUGGAGUUGUCUGUAAUAAUCUUGAAAGGCCCAAGGGCCUGUCCCCAUCCUGACUUAAAGGCAUCUGCUUCCCUGUUUCAUAUCACAUGACAGAGAAACCUGUUCUCAUGGCAUGUAACAUCCCUGUGAAGAGAGCGUUGUAUAUGAUUUUGUAUUUUUUAAUUCAUUUUAAUCUACAGGUUGGAAUCUAAUUUUUAAAUUUUAUUGGAACUCACAUUUUAAAAAGAAAUAAAAUUUAAAAUAAUAAUAAUAAUAAUAAUAAUAAUAAUAAACCUUUGACCAGUGUCUUCCAAGUAGUUUGAUCAAAGAAUUUAUAGGUGUUUUCAAAACACAGUCCGGAGUGUAAAGAUUGGAAAGCCCCAUGGCCUUGCCUGUGUGUAUGAAGUGUAAAUCUGGUUUUGUUUUGUUGUUUUGGAUUCUUUUGGGUUUUUGUUUUGUUUUGAAGAUCAGACAGUGAUCACUCUGAAAGAUUGAAGCCAAGAAUUUGUAACUAUGGUAUUUACUGUAAGCUGUAGAACACUCAAUAACUAUUAAAAAAAAAAAUUCCCCCCCAAAAAAAAGUCUUAGGUGACUAGACUGAGUGGUUCUUGGGGAGGGAGGCACAGAGGACUGUCCUGGGCCAGUGAGUCCCUUGGGCGUCUCCCCAAGUUGAUGCUAAAUUUGUUCUCAGUAGUCAAGAAAAACCUAUGGUACAUCUUACAGCUGAUCUGACAGGGGUCUGCCCUAAGGGUCUCACAGCUGCUGGGGAGCUUUAAGUGGCAACUUCAGCACCCACCCUAAGUGUGUGAUGUGGGAGCACAGUGAGGCCAUUCAGAGUUGAAAUCCAUUGAGCCAUCCGCGCAAUAAAGCUGACAUCUAUUGUGUG